AGUCGCUAUGCGUGUGCUUGUGGGUGGCGGGACAGGCUUCAUUGGGACAGCCCUAACCCAGCUGCUGAAUGCCAGAGGCCACGAAGUGACGUUGGUCUCCCGAAAGCCCGGGCCCGGCCGGAUCACGUGGGAUGAGCUCGCUGCAUCGGGGCUGCCGAGCUGCGAUGCCGCCGUCAACCUGGCCGGAGAGAACAUCCUCAACCCUCUCCGAAGGUCAGCCCGGGCCCUAAAGCUGAUACCCACUAGAGCACAGGGAGGACAGUGCCCCACUGAUGAGAACCUAUGGAAUGAAACCUUCCAAAAAGAGGUAAUCGGCAGCCGCCUAGAGACCACCCAAUUGCUGGCUAAAGCCAUCACCAAAGCCCCACAACCCCCCAAGGCCUGGGUCUUAGUCACAGGUGUAGCUUACUACCAGCCCAGUCUGACUGCGGAGUAUGAUGAAGACAGCCCAGGAGGGGACUUUGACUUUUUCUCCAACCUCGUAACCAAAUGGGAAGCUGCAGCCAGGCUUCCUGGAGAUUCUACACGCCAGGUGGUGGUGCGCUCAGGGGUUGUGCUGGGCCGUGGGGGUGGUGCCAUGGGCCACAUGCUGCUGCCCUUUCGCCUGGGCCUGGGGGGCCCCAUCGGCUCAGGCCACCAAUUCUUCCCCUGGAUACACAUCGGGGACCUGGCAGGAAUCCUGACCCAUGCCCUUGAAGCAAACCACGUGCACGGGGUCCUGAAUGGAGUGGCUCCAUCCUCCGCCACUAAUGCUGAGUUUGCCCAGACCUUGGGUGCUGCCCUGGGCCGCCGAGCCUUCAUCCCUCUCCCCAGCGCUGUGGUGCAAGCUGUCUUUGGGCGACAGCGUGCCAUCAUGCUGCUGGAGGGCCAGAAGGUGAUCCCACAGCGAACACUGGCCACUGGCUACCAGUAUUCCUUCCCAGAGCUAGGGGCUGCCUUAAAGGAAAUUGUAGCCUAAGUAGGUCGUGGCAAGGGCCUGAGGCCUGUUCCUCACAGGCUUCCAGGUUAGGCACUGUGAAUAGGCUCAGCUCCUCUAGAGAGCUGAAGCCAUCUGGUUCUUAGAUUCCUCUCCCAGUCCUCUUUCCCAUUGUUCUGUUGCUCCACCUUAUUGUCUCAAGGCCGUAAUCUCAUCAGGUUGGGACAUUAAUCUUUUCAACUCCUUGUAAGAUUUCCCAGUUUGGUUUCUCUACAUGUCCUGCAGCUGCCCCACUUCUCCUUUACGCUGUGUAGAGAAUGCUCUGCAGUUUAGGCAAUAAAAAUAAAUUGUCUCACUAA